AUGAUGGUGCGGGGAAGGCACCGCGGCCUUGGCCAGCUGAGUCGCGACGGCCGCCGGGGCGGCGGCAGUGGCCGCGGCAGCGGCGGUGGUAGCGGGCUCCCCAGCGGCAUGCCAGUGCCCCCCGGGCGCGAUGGCUAG